AAAUUGCCUGCAGUGUUGAGUAUGCAGUACGGGUUAGUAGCCCAGGAGCAAUAGGCUAUAUGCUAUAGAGCCUAGGUGUAUGGUAGGCAAUACCAUCUAGGUGUGUGUAAGGACACCCUAUGAUGUUUGCACAGUGAUGAAAUUGCCUAAGGACGUGUUUCUCAGAGCAUAUUCCCAUCGUUAAGUGAUGCAUGGCUGUAUAGUUACUUACCUGUUUUUCCAAUGGAUGAAUGUUUCUGAUGGGGUGGGUUUCUGUGCCUAGCACAGGGUAGGUGUCAAAUACGUGUUUGUUGAGUGGAAGAAGGAAUCACAUGAUGAUUUAGAUUGACAGUAGGUCAAAAUAAUACUCAUUUCUUAUGUACUUUUAGGAGUAUAGGUGAAAAUAAUAGGAACAAUGCAGAAGAAAAUCCUUUUGAAAACCUUCCCAAAAUGUUGACUGGAAAAGAGUUUAAACUUACUCAUUUCAAGCUGCUAUUGUAUCUCUCUCUCUCUCUCUCUCUCUAUCUAUCUAUAUAUAUAGGAAUUUUUAAAAAAUACACCGAAAGAAUAGAAACAUAUCAACACUAUACUUAACACAUGUACUCUGCAUUAGGUUUUAAUUCCAUGAAUUCCUAUUCAUUUUUUAUUUUUAUGCAUGAAAGUUUACUGGGUAAUGGAAUUUACCAUCCCUGUUUAGAUUCUGCAUUGAUGACAUAUCCUGUUCAAUGUCAUAACCCCUAAUUAUUAACCGUGUUCACCCCAAAUGGAUCCAUUUAUGAUACAUGGAGAAAUAACUUGUUUUUCUUCUUGGUCAAUUUGUGCCUAUAUCGACUGAUGACAUUGUGCCUUGUUCAGAAAACGUAAUCACAAGUUCUUGAAAAAAAUAAUAAAACAUGUAAAAGUCAGCUGGCAUUUCAGAAUCUAAGUCCCUUUUUAAUUCCCAAAAUACAUGAAACACUAUUUUCUUGGUAUUUUCUCAUGUACUUUGCUACUUUAACAAAGAUUAAUUCAUUUAAGUCUUAAUUUUUUAAAAAAUGUCUCAAGUGUCUCUUUUUUCAGGUAGCAUGAAUAUUUCAAGAUAAAAGAAGACAGCUUGGUUCCUAACUAAGCCUGUCCUUCCUGACCUGGGUAUUUAUUUCAUUCUUAUAUUUCUUCAAGAGUAAAGUAAGACCAAAGGAGGUAUAGCUGCCCCCCAAAAAUCAUAGUUCUGUUUGAGGAAUUGUUUCCCUCAAGGAAAGAGAAGAUAACACCUGAAAUAUGUCAAGGAAUUAAUUGUUAAUGAUUUCUGUGUACAAAUAUUUUAAGUUGGGAGUGUUGAGAAAAUUGCAAUUUAUAUAGGAACUUCUUUGCCCUUUCUGAAGCCAUUCUUUAGAAAAAAAUUCAAAAUCUUAUCACAGUUCACAUAUGGGAAGUUAUUUUGCUUUAAAAUGAAUUAAGAACAAGAAUAAUGUUUUAAAAUCUAUAUUCCUUUUAAUGUGUAAAUCAAAGAAAAUAUCUGAGGCAAGUCUCAAUUAUUUCGUGAGGUUUAUUUGCCAAAGUUAAGGAUAUGUGCCUGGGAGGCAGGUCUAUGCCUUUCUCUGAAGAUGAUUUUGAGGGCUUCAGUAUUUAAAGGAGAAAGGGCAGGAUAUUGGGAAAUACACAAUUUUCAUAUGAGAAAUCGGUAGGGGAAAACAUUCAUGCCUUUGUCUGAAUCAGCGAAUCUGUAUUUUUACAUAAGACAACAUAGACAAAUACAGCAGAAGAAGCAGUGAGAUAUACAUUUGUCUCAGGUGAGUGGAGGGAUGAUUUUGAGUCCUGUCCUAUGUCCCCACGCCUGUGAAGAUAAGCUAUCAAUUCACAUUGCCUUGGUGACCUUCAACAGAACUGCUUUAGGGUAGAGAUCUCGGGGCCCACAAGGAUUUCUUCAGGGGCCAAGUGUGAGGGAGGUGUGUAGCUUUUCAUCUUUGUAGCCAUCUUAUCUAGGAACCAUAAUGGGAGGCAGGUUUGCAUGACCCAGCUUGACUUUUCCUUUAGGCUUAGUGAGUCUGGGGUUCCAAGAUUUAUUUUCCUUUCACAGAUGUCUUUAUGUGUAAGGAUUUAGAUGUUUUAUCUGAUCAGGAAGAUUAUAAAAGUGCCAGUUUAGUGAUUUUUAGGAAGUGAUUACUGCAUGAACACACGUUCUUGAACUUUCCUCCAAUCACACGAUGUUAAACUGCUUGUGUAAAUAAGAGCUUAGACCAGUGGAUCUCAAACUCUAGAGAGCUUCAGACUCACCGUGAAGACUUGCUAAAACACAGAUUGCUGGGCUCUACCCUCAAGGUUUCCGAGUCUGUAGUCCUGGGAAGGGAUUUAUAAAUUUGCAUUUCUAACAGGUUUCUACGUGAUGCUGAUGCUGCUGGUCCCCACACUCUGAGAACCACAGAUUGAAACUGUUUGGUUAAAUUAGUGGUUAUCAACCCUGGUUCCGCCCUUACACACUUGAAGAGUCAAGGCCUUAGGGUGGGGGAUGGGCCACAGAGUCAGGUGCUGCUAAUGAGGUGGGGCAAGUAUUUAAAUCUUCAGGAUGUGGAUGUAGUUUGAGAAAGCCCUUCAAAUAACUGGUUGUUUUCUUCUAUUCUCUCUCCCCCUUUGAAACCACUCUCCUCUACCCCUCAAUAGGAGAGUCCUGGUGCAAAUGAAACAGUGCUCAUGGAUUGUUUUAGUCCUCUCCCAGAAAAUAAAACACAGCCUUUACCAACAGUUGCCCCAAUGCUUCUUAAGGAGUUCAGUAGAGGAAGAAGUAGUUAAAUUGCAGCAUAAGGCCAAGAAAGGCCUUCCUUCUGGUCAUUUCUUUUUCCAUUUUUGUUUAGAGCACUGUACUAUUAGAUCUGUCAAUUAAUCACUGUAGAUAUUAGCCUGAGUAGUGUUCAUGGCUAUAGCUUCUUCAUAUAUUUCCCUUGCUGGGCCAAAUUGACUUAAAUUUCCCAAGACAUUAAAAAAUGUGUAUUAUUUAAUUCCCAAAACAAUCCCAUAGGGGUAGAGAUCCCCACUGCACAGAUGAAGGAAUGGAGACUUAGAGUAGUUAAAGAAUUUCCGGGGUCACACUGUAAGUAGUCAUCUCUGGCUCCAUUAGGUUGUGUGAACUUGGCUAAGGUCCAUAACCUCCAUGUGUAAAGUUUCCUCGUCUGUGGAAUGAGAAUGAUACUGGUACCUACCUUCUGAGGUUGUUUUGAGAACUAAAUAAAGAGUUACUACACAGAGUUGUGUACAUACACGUAAUAAAUGCUCAGUAAAUGUUAUCUCUUAGUUGGCUAACUCCUAGUUGGUACUUUUUAAGUUCGGGGUAAUCCUGCCUUUUCUUUUUCUUUUUUUUUGAGAUGAGGUCUCACUCUGUCGCCCAGGCUAGAGUGCAGUGGCACAAUCGUAGCUCACUGCAGCCUCGACCUCCAGGGCUCGAGUGAUCUUCCUGCCUCGACCUCCCAAAGCACUGGGAUUGCAGGCAAAUGCCACCACACCUGGGUAAUUUUUUAAUUUUUUUUUUUGUAGAGAUGGAUACCUGCCAUGUAGCCCAGGCUGGUCUUGAACUCCUGGCCUCAAGUGAUCUGCCCACCUCAGCCUCCCAAAGUGCUGGGAUUAUGGGCAUGAGCCACUGCGCCUGGCCUAUCCUGCCUUUGUGCCAGGCAGUCCUCCUCAUGUGUAUUACAGCUGUUUUCACUCAUUAGCUCCUGAGGUAAACAAAUUGAAAAAAUGAGCGAACUGGAACAGUUGAGGCAAGAAGCAGAACAACUGCGGAAUCAGAUUCAGGAUGCUCGGAAAGCAUGUAAUGAUGCAACGCUUGUUCAGAUUACAUCAAAUAUGGACUCUGUGGGUCGAAUACAAAUGCGAACAAGACGUACACUGAGGGGCCACCUAGCUAAAAUCUAUGCUAUGCAUUGGGGAUACGAUUCCAGGCUGCUAGUCAGUGCUUCUCAAGAUGGAAAAUUAAUUAUUUGGGAUAGCUAUACAACAAAUAAGAUGCAUGCUAUUCCUUUGAGGUCCUCCUGGGUGAUGACCUGUGCUUAUGCUCCCUCUGGUAAUUAUGUUGCCUGUGGAGGCUUGGACAACAUCUGCUCUAUAUAUAACUUAAAGACCAGAGAGGGAAAUGUGAGAGUAAGCCGAGAGUUGCCAGGUCACACAGGGUACUUGUCCUGCUGUCGUUUUUUAGAUGACAGCCAAAUUGUUACAAGUUCAGGAGAUACAACUUGUGCUUUAUGGGACAUCGAAACUGCCCAGCAGACCACCACAUUCACUGGGCAUUCUGGAGAUGUGAUGAGUCUUUCUUUGAGUCCUGACAUGAGGACUUUUGUUUCUGGUGCUUGUGAUGCCUCUUCCAAAUUAUGGGAUAUUCGAGAUGGAAUGUGUAGACAGUCUUUCACGGGACAUGUCUCAGAUAUCAAUGCUGUCAGUUUUUUCCCAAAUGGAUAUGCCUUCGCCACUGGCUCUGAUGAUGCCACUUGCCGGCUCUUUGACCUUCGUGCAGAUCAAGAGUUAUUAUUGUAUUCUCAUGACAAUAUCAUCUGUGGAAUCACUUCUGUAGCCUUCUCAAAAAGUGGGCGUCUCUUGUUGGCUGGUUACGAUGACUUUAAUUGUAAUGUAUGGGACACGCUAAAAGGAGAUCGUGCAGGUGUCCUUGCUGGUCAUGACAACCGUGUGAGCUGCUUAGGUGUAACUGAUGAUGGCAUGGCUGUGGCAACAGGCUCUUGGGACAGUUUUCUUAGAAUCUGGAAUUAACAGUGUCAUACAUAUUUGUUCUCCAUUGAUAUAUCUGGAGAAAUCAAUGCUACAGCCUAUAGCUGUGAAAAAAUUCUACCUUAUAUUUGCAGGUGAAGAUUUUUCUAUUAGAUUAUCUACAAAAACAAGCUUUCAGUAAACUACCAAAAAAAAAGUGGGGGUGGAGGAAAAAAGGCAAAGGCGCCUUCUGAGAUCAAAAGGACCAGUGUAUUAAUUUGAGGGGUUGGGUUAUUUUAACCUUGGUGAAUUGUUGUGUGUACUCAGAGUGUAUUUUCUUUGUGUAGAACAGAAUGUACACAUUAUAGCAGCUCGCCAUUGUGUUUGCAUUUUUUAAGAAGUACAUUUUUAACUUUGUAUACACAAGAAAUGUCAUAUUUUUGAGUUUUGUAAUGGAAGAACCAGGCACAGAAACAGACAGAAAUGAUACUGUAUGUGUGUGUAUUUAUGUCUGAAGAAAGUCCCCUUGAAUUCUGAUAUCUCUUUGAAUCUAAGAGAUCCUGAUAGCUUCAUGUUUAAGAGCAUUGACAGGUGGGGCACCUCUGAGGGGAGUUCAUUGUUUCUCAUGCAUCAUUUGCCAUAUACUAUUAAUCAAAGUGCUUGCUUUCAGUCCUUUGAGGGGACAGAUAAUCUGAAGGCCAGAGAUUAGAGAUUUCACUGAUAUUUUGGACAUACAUAAGAAACAUCAUUAUAAUUAAUAAAAAGUAGGUAAUAGCAUAUAAAUGGUUCUUGACAUUUUAAAAGCCUGGUUAUGAUCAGUUGACACUUUGAGUACCCCCCUAAAUAGCUGGACUUUCCUUUUCAUUUCAUAUUUGGAACUAAGUUUGUAGCGUAUACUCAUCUUUCAGAAGUUUGGUAAACAUUGGGAUUGUCCCUGCAUCUGAACAUCUUUCCCAGUGCUAUCAGUAUACAUCUAGAGAGGAAAUGCAAUGUGACAGUGUUACAUUUGGAGAGAAGUGUGAAAUCUAACCAAUCGCUAGCACAUAUUUGUUGUAAUACGGUGGUUUAUUUCAUGUUUGCAUACUAUAAAAUCUGAAUUGAUGUGAAAUAUCUGUGCCUUUAAAUUUCUUAAACCUUUAAGCUUUUUGUUCUGUUUUGCAACAUUUUGUAGUAUUUCUUCCCUUCCUUAGCACAAAAUACUGGUUUCUAAGUGGUUUUGCUUCAAAGGAUGUCUAGAUGUAAGUGAUUCCACUUAAAGCCAAAAUAAAAAUUCCUAAAGCAGUUCUUAAAGGAGUUAGAGAGCUAUAUUAAACAGUUUUUCUGUGGUAUAAUAAUGUGUCUCUUACUAGAAGUCCCCCACGACCAAGUUAAAGAUACUUUUCCUGUUGGAUUCUCUUUUACAAAUAAGUCUAAAUGACUGAUAAUAGAAGAUUGUUAGUCUUGCUUGAUGGUAAAGUCUUGGAUUAUUCUGAUAUAUAGACGUGCAUUGUUUUGUAACUUAGUUACUUUUCAGAUAGGUCUGUGUUAACUUUUGAACAUGUGUAACUUAACCUAAAUACUCCCAAACUUUACCUCUAAAUUUUUGUUUUUAUGUUGUGAAUGUGCUAAUAUGUGCAUCAACUGUAAAGAUGUAUCAGUUUUAUUAAAAUCAGUUGACAAUUAGAAUAAUAAAGUGGAUAAAGGCAAAUUAAGAUAUAGGACCAAAACAGAAUAUUGUAGAUGGCAGUUAUGAAUGUAUAUUUAUAUUUUGAUUAAGAUUUCUAUUAACUUUUUGGCUGGGCAGAGUGGCUUACACCUAUAAUCCCAGCAAUUUGGGAGGCCAAGGUGGGCAGAUCACUUGAGGUCAGGAGUUCGCGACCAGCCUACCCAACAUGGUGAAACCCCAUCUCUUCUAAAAAUACAAACAUUAGCCGGGCGUGGUGGCACAUUCCUGUAAUCCCAGCUACUCGGGAGGCUGAGGCAGGAGAUUCGCCUGAACCCGGGAGGCAGAGGUUGCAGUGAGCCGAGAUUGUGCCACUGCACUCCAGCCUAGGCGACAGAGUGAGACUCCAUCUCAAAUUGGAAAAAAAAAAAAUUAUAUGAACUUUUGCUAUUAAUGUUUAUUUGUAGGCUAUUUAUAUCACUUCAUAAAGAACAGUUCUUUGAGAAAAGAAUAAAGGAAUGUAUUCAUUUCCAGAAAAAGAGGGUUGGGGAAAGUUUGCCAUGUAGGUUAGUCAGAAGAAAGCAAUUCUAUUAUGCAUAAAAAUAACCUUAAAUAUGUAAGAGAGUAUCUCCUCUACUUAAAAGUUAUUAUAGUAGUCACAGGCAUACAGACCACAGGAAUUCUAUGGUCUUAACAUAUUUUAAAAUUACAUUUAUUUUAAUGUUCUUAAAGUUUAUGAAGAGGAGUUUAAAGCAAUUCCCAUAAUUAAAUAUUUACUCGGCAACUAAAAACUAUUUAACACUUGUGGUUAAUUAUACACAUAAACAAAUGGCGACAGAGUAGCCUCACUACCACAAUUACUUCAUGGUUACACCUUUGCUUUCUAAUAAUAGGGGCUCCAGUUGCUAAAUAUAUUUGUUUACUUACAGUUUAAGUUGAGCUGAUUGUUGAAUUCUGUUAUUGUUCCUGAAUUCAAUGAGUAUAUAAUUUGUAGAGAUGUUGAAUAGUUUGGAUCUUAGUUUUUAAGGCUGAAAAAUCUGGCUGGAUUUAGUUUUUAAAAAUUUGCAUCAUCAAGAAUAUUGCAGUUAAUGUUCCUUUUUUUUUUUUUUUAAAGACAGAGUCUCACUCUGUCACCCAGGCUGGAGUGUACAGUGGUGUGAUUUUGGCUCAUUGCAACCUCAACCUCUGCCUCCUGGGUUCAAGCAAUUCUUGUGCCUCAGCCUCCCAAGUAGCUGGGACUAUAGGCAUGUGCCACCAUGCCCGGCUAAUUUUUGUAUUUUUAGUAGAGAUGGGGUUUCACCAUCUUGGCCAGUCUGAUCUCGUACUCCUGGCCUCAAGUGAUCCACCAGCCUCAGCCUCCCAAAGUGCUGGGAUUACAGACGUGAGCCACCGUGCCCAGCCAGGUUUCCUUCUUUACCUUCUAAGAAACAUUUAAACAUAAUGUGCCUGAGAAGGUUAAUUUGUUGACUCUGUAGCAUGUCAAGAAGAGUAGUUUUUUGAGAUCUGGCAAGAAUAUUUUAGAGAUACAUAUUCUUUUCUAAGUAUGUUAUCACCCUGUGGUGUUGAGCAUAUCGUCCCAAAAACCUGCUUCAGCAAGCAGUUCUUGGCCAGGCAUGGUGGCUCACACCUGUAAUCCCAGCACUUUGGGAGGCCGAGGCAGGUGGAUCACGAGGUCAGGAGUUCAAGACCAGCCUGGCCAAGAUGGUGAAACCCCAUCUCUACUAAAAAUACAAAAAUUAGCCGGGCGUGGAGGUGGGCGCCUGUCAGCUACUCGUGAGGCUGAGGCAGAGAAUUACUUGAACUCAGGAGGUGGAGGUUUUGGUGAGCUGAGAUGGCGCCACUGCACUCCAACCCGAGCGACAGAGCAAGAUUCCGUCCCAAAAAGAAAAAGCAGUUUUUGCCAUCAGCAAGGAUAUCUCCUCCACUUUAAUGGACAGGCCUCAUUUUUGGCAGCUAUGCUGUUUGAGAUGUAGACUGAAUAUCCAAGGUUCCUCCCUAGCUCAAGUUUUUACUUGUGAUUACACACACCACAUUGAAUUCCGUCUUCAGAGGCAAAGAUUUGGGCUUCAUAUCUCAACAGCAAAAGGGCCUGUUCAGCAAUUCCCUUCAUUUUAGACUCAUAUGACCUCAGCGAUUGCAUGAUAGUAGUAAACUAGUCUCCUGGAAAUAAUGGAUGUAGGUGCUUCUAGAAUAUGUUACAGAAUUUCAGACUUAACCUAUUAAUAGAUAAAUGGAUCUUGACUUAAGGUGACAAAAUGAAACUUUUAUUAUUGCUUAAAAAUGCUGUGCCAAUAUUGUAUAACUAGCUCCUCUAAUACUUUUGGUAUUUUGGAUUUAAUAAUAAGACCUUAAGCAUUUUAAAUGUGAACAUGUUCAGGGAAGUAUGCUUUGAUGUAAAUGUCUCAGAUCUAAGUUGUAACACAAUUGAAUACUUGUGGCUUAUUCUUGGUUUAACUUAGGAAAACUGGUUAAACAAUCCCCCAUUUGGGCCUGUCAUCAUUUUAAUAGUGACGAUGUUCUUUCUGAAAUCUUCAGGGUCGGAGUCAGGCUGAAUUUUUUUAAAAAUUAAAUAUUAUGUUCAAAUUCUUUCCUUUUUGCCAUUGUGAAAAAGCAAAAUUUUAAAUGAUUUCUCCUGUUAGAAUUUUUAAAAAUACCCACAGGUUGGACCAUCUUUCUUAUGGGUUGCACAAUGAAUUUAUAUUUUAAAUUAGAUUAAGUAGAAUGUGAAGUACAUUUCAGAUUUACUAGUUUUCUUUCCAUUGUUCAUUUUGGGUUGCCUCAGAUUCAGUGUAUAUUUUAAAAUAUUGGUUACAUAAUAGGUACUCAAUGAAAUGGUUUAUAGUAGAAUAUCUAAGCUAGCACUUUAUUUUAAAAAGUAACUUAUUAAUUAAUCACACAUUGAUGGUACACCUUGUAUUUAGCAAAUGUUUGCAUGUUGAUAAAAUCUCCUAUGUCUUCUUUCUUAAAUCCAGUUGCUGAUUUUGUAAAAUACAGUUGUGAUAAAGCAGCAUUACGGGGGGGAAAAAGCUAUAUUCCAACUGGUGUUAAAUGUAUUCAACAAAAUCUUACAUCAUACAGUAUUUAUUUCUUAAUUAAUAGAACUUCAGUGAUAUACUUGGUAGAUAUCUCAAGCCUUUUGUCUUUUACACAAUGGUGCUCUAUCCUAUUGUUUUCUUUUCAAAGAAGCAUCUGAACACUUGCAUUUCUAUUUUCCUAUCCAAAGGCAUCCACAUCUAAGUGUGUUUUUAAAGUUGAUUAAAAUUAUUUUUCUGUUAAAGCAUUCUGAAAGUGUUUGUCUUUACCUAGAAUGAUUUGUACACACUCGUGGUCAACUGAACAUGAAUGUCAGUAGUAGUCUAAUUAUGGGAAGGGUAAACGUGUUAGAUUAAGGCUCUUAAAGCUCUAAACCAUAUAAACUAUGGACUUGUAUCAUGAUUUAACUGUUCUUAGAUCUUUCUUACACAGUGAUUCAUUCCUCUAUUUGUACAGUGGCUUUAUGAAAUGUUGUGAAUUGAUACUGUAAUCAAUAAAGUGCUUUUAACCAGA